GGAGCUCGGCUAACUCGGCGCCCAGUGCACGGCCGCACCAUGGGGUCCCGCCACUUCGAGGGGAUUUAUGACCACGUGGGGCACUUCGGCAGAUUCCAGAGAGUCCUCUAUUUCAUAUGUGCCUUCCAGAACAUCUCUUGUGGUAUUCACUACUUGGCUUCUGUGUUCAUGGGAGUCACCCCUCAUCAUGUCUGCAGGCCCCCAGGCAAUGUGAGUCAGGUUGUUUUCCAUAAUCACUCUAAUUGGAGUUUGGAGGACACCGGGGCCCUGUUGUCUUCAGGCCAGAAAGAUUAUGUUACGGUGCAGUUGCAGAAUGGUGAGAUCUGGGAGCUCUCAAGGUGUAGCAGGAAUAAGAGGGAGAACACAUCGAGUUUGGGCUAUGAAUACACUGGCAGUAAGAAAGAGUUUCCUUGUGUGGAUGGCUACAUAUAUGACCAGAACACAUGGAAAAGCACUGCGGUGACCCAGUGGAACCUGGUCUGUGACCGAAAAUGGCUUGCAAUGCUGAUCCAGCCCCUAUUUAUGUUUGGAGUCCUACUGGGAUCGGUGACUUUUGGCUACUUUUCUGACAGGCUAGGACGCCGGGUGGUCUUGUGGGCCACAAGCAGUAGCAUGUUUUUGUUUGGAAUAGCAGCGGCGUUUGCAGUUGAUUAUUACACCUUCAUGGCUGCUCGCUUUUUUCUUGCCAUGGUUGCAAGUGGCUAUCUUGUGGUGGGGUUUGUCUAUGUGAUGGAAUUCAUUGGCAUGAAGUCUCGGACAUGGGCGUCUGUCCAUUUGCAUUCCUUUUUUGCAGUUGGAACCCUGCUGGUGGCUUUGACAGGAUACUUGGUCAGGACCUGGUGGCUUUACCAGAUGAUCCUCUCCACAGUGACUGUCCCCUUUAUCCUGUGCUGUUGGGUGCUCCCAGAGACACCUUUUUGGCUUCUCUCAGAGGGACGAUAUGAAGAAGCACAAAAAAUAGUUGACAUCAUGGCCAAGUGGAACAGGGCAAGCUCCUGUAAACUGUCAGAACUUUUAUCACUGGACCUACAAGGUCCUGUUAGUAAUAGCCCCACUGAAGUUCAGAAGCACAACCUAUCAUAUCUGUUUUAUAACUGGAGCAUUACGAAAAGGACACUUACCGUUUGGCUAAUCUGGUUCACUGGAAGUUUGGGAUUCUACUCGUUUUCCUUGAAUUCUGUUAACUUAGGAGGCAAUGAAUACUUAAACCUCUUCCUCCUGGGUGUAGUGGAAAUUCCCGCCUACACCUUCGUGUGCAUCGCCAUGGACAAGGUCGGGAGGAGAACAGUCCUGGCCUACUCUCUUUUCUGCAGUGCACUGGCCUGUGGUGUCGUUAUGGUGAUCCCCCAGAAACAUUAUAUUUUGGGUGUGGUGACAGCUAUGGUUGGAAAAUUUGCCAUCGGGGCAGCAUUUGGCCUCAUUUAUCUUUAUACAGCUGAGCUGUAUCCAACCAUUGUAAGAUCGCUGGCUGUGGGAAGCGGCAGCAUGGUGUGUCGCCUGGCCAGCAUCCUGGCGCCGUUCUCUGUGGACCUCAGCAGCAUUUGGAUCUUCAUACCACAGCUCCUAGGACAGCACCUUCAGGAGUAAUAAUGCAGGCAGUAGCUGGCAAUUAAGGAGGCACUCCAUGGUGGGUCAUGAAGGAAUGAAUGAGUGAGUGAUGAGAUUAAACCUCGUUGAUGAGGAAAAGAACUCGAAGUCCAGCACAAGUAACCAAAGAUCUCACCGAGUAAUCACAGUGACAACUGUUAUGUCAAAUUCAAAUCCAUUACCCUCUGAAAACAGUUAGGAAAUUCUAUUCUCCGAAGGGUUCGUUCCUUUCUUGAUGUGUCACUUAUCAUUAUUUUUAAUUCCUUCUAGUUGUUUGUUGGGACUAUGGCCCUCCUGAGUGGAGUGUUAACACUAAAGCUUCCAGAAACCCUUGGGAAACGGCUAGCAACUACUUGGGAGGAGGCUGCAAAACUGGAGUCAGAGAAUGAAAGCAAGUCAAGCAAAUUACUUCUCACAACUAAUAAUAGUGGGCUGGAAAAAACGGAAGCGAUUACCCCCAGGGAUUCUGGUCUUGGUGAAUAAAUGUGCCAUGCCUGCUGUCUAGCACCUGAAAUAUUAUUUACCCUAAUGCCUUUGUAUUAGAGGAAUCUUAUUCUCAUCUCCCAUAUGUUGUUUGUAUGUCUUUUUAAUAAAUUUUGUAAGAAAAUUUUAAAGCAAAUAUGUUAUAAAAGAAAUAAAAACUAAGAUGAAAAUUCUCAGUUUUAAAAA